AAGGAAGAGUCUAGGCUGAGCAACAUGAAGGGGCCCCCAACCUUCUGCAGCCUCCUGCUGCUGUCAUUGCUCCUGAGCCCAGACCCUACAGCAGCAUUCCUACUGCCACCCAGCACUGCCUGCUGUACUCAGCUCUACCGAAAGCCACUCUCAGACAAGCUACUGAGGAAGGUCAUCCAGGUGGAACUGCAGGAGGCUGACGGGGACUGUCACCUCCAGGCUUUCGUGCUUCACCUGGCUCAACGCAGCAUCUGCAUCCACCCCCAGAACCCCAGCCUGUCACAGUGGUUUGAGCACCAAGAGAGAAAGCUCCAUGGGACUCUGCCCAAGCUGAAUUUUGGGAUGCUAAGGAAAAUGGGCUGAAGCCCCCAAUAGCCAAAUAAUAAAGCAGCAUUGGAUAAUAAUUUCUGAGUAUAA